GUCCCCCUUCUCCAGGGCUGUUGGGGAGGAACAGGAUCGCAUCGAAUGGGACCCACCUGUGACCAACUGCUCACAGGGCCUCCCCGAGCCCCCCUGCAGGAACCGGGGGGCCAAAGACCCCUCCCCAGGCAGUCCGUGCAGUCCUGUCCCAGGAAGCUGGGCUGCCUCCGAGUCCAUCCAAAGCCACGGCCUGCGGCGCCCGCGGCACCAUGAUCUCCACCAAGGAGAAGAACAAGAUCCCGAAGGACAGCAUGACGCUUCUGCCCUGCUUCUACUUCGUGGAGCUGCCCAUAGUGGCUUCUUCCAUCGUAUCCUUGUACUUCCUGGAGCUGACCGACCUCUUCAAGCCGGCCAAGGUGGGCUUCCAGUGCUAUGACCGCACUCUCUCCAUGCCCUACGUGGAGACCAACGAGGAGCUCAUCCCGCUGCUGAUGCUGCUCAGCUUGGCCUUCGCGGCCCCUGCCGCCUCGAUCAUGGUGGCCGAGGGCAUGUUGUACUGUCUGCAGUCCCGGCUGUGGGGCCGUGCCGGGGGGCCCGCCGGGGCGGAGGGCAGCAUCAACGCCGGCGGCUGCAACUUCAACUCCUUCCUGCGGCGUACGGUGCGGUUUGUGGGUGUCCACGUGUUCGGCCUGUGUGCCACAGCCCUGGUGACGGACGUGAUCCAGCUGGCCACGGGUUACCACACUCCCUUCUUCCUCACCGUCUGCAAGCCCAACUACACUCUCCUGGGCACGUCCUGCGAGGUCAACCCCUACAUCACGCAGGACAUCUGCUCCGGCCACGACAUCCACGCCAUCCUGUCUGCACGGAAGACCUUCCCGUCCCAGCACGCCACGCUGUCAGCCUUCGCCGCGGUCUAUGUGUCGGUGAGUCCGGCCCCUCACUGCCCUUCCCAGGCCCUCUUGCUGACCCGUGGGGAGCCCUCCCUGACCCCAACCCCCAUGCCCCAGAUGUACUUCAACUCGGUCAUCUCGGACACCACCAAGCUGCUGAAGCCCAUCCUGGUCUUCGCCUUUGCCAUCGCCGCGGGCGUAUGCGGGCUCACGCAGAUCACGCAGUACCGCAGCCACCCUGUGGACGUGUAUGCCGGCUUCCUCAUCGGGGCGGGCAUCGCUGCCUACCUGGCCUGCCACGCGGUGGGCAACUUCCAGGCCCCACCUGCAGAGAAGCCCGCGGCCCCGGCCCCCGCCAAGGACGCGCUGCGGGCCCUGACGCAGCGGGGCCACGACUCGGUUUAUCAGCAGAAUAAGUCGGUGAGCACCGACGAGCUGGGGCCCCCAGGGCGGCUGGAGGGCGCGCCCCGGCCCGUGGCCCGCGAGAAGACCUCGCUGGGCAGCCUGAAGCGCGCCAGCGUGGACGUGGACCUGCUGGCCCCGCGCAGCCCCAUGGCCAAGGAGAACAUGGUGACCUUCAGCCACACGCUGCCCAGGGCCAGCGCGCCCUCGCUGGACGACCCCGCGCGCCGCCACAUGACCAUCCACGUGCCGCUGGACGCCUCGCGCUCCAAGCAGCUCAUCAGCGAGUGGAAGCAGAAGAGCCUGGAGGGCCGCGGCCUGGGGCUGCCCGACGACGCCAGCCCCGGGCACCUGCGCGCGCCCGCCGAACCCAUGGCGGAGGAGGAGGAAGAGGAGGAGGACGAAGAGGAAGAGGAGGAGGAGGAAGAGGAGGAGGACGAGGGCCCGGCCCCGCCCUCGCUCUACCCCACCGUGCAGGCGCGGCCGGGGCUGGGGCCUCGGGUCAUCCUCCCACCGCGCGCGGGGCCGCCGCCGCUGGUGCACAUCCCGGAGGAGGGCGCGCAGACGGGGGCCGGCCUGUCCCCCAAAAGCGGCGCCGGGGUGCGCGCCAAGUGGCUCAUGAUGGCCGAGAAGAGCGGGGCGGCAGUGGCCAACCCUCCGCGGCUGCUGCAGGUCAUCGCCAUGUCCAAGGCUCCGGGCGCGCCGGGCCCCAAGGCGGCCGAGACGGCGUCGUCGUCCAGCGCCAGCUCCGACUCCUCGCAGUACCGGUCGCCGUCGGACCGCGACUCCGCCAGCAUCGUGACCAUCGACGCGCACGCGCCGCACCACCCCGUGGUGCACCUGUCGGCCGGCGGCGCGCCCUGGGAGUGGAAGGCGGCGGGCGGCGGGGCCAAGGCGGAGGCCGACGGCGGCUACGAGCUGGGGGACCUGGCGCGCGGCUUCCGCGGCGGGGCCAAGCCCCCGGGCGUGUCCCCCGGCUCGUCGGUCAGCGACGUGGACCAGGAGGAGCCGCGGUUCGGGGCCGUGGCCACCGUCAACCUGGCCACGGGCGAGGGGCUGCCCCCGCUGGGCGCGGCCGAUGGGGCGCUGGGCCCGGGCAGCCGGGAGUCCACGCUGCGGCGCCACGCGGGCGGCCUGGGGCUGGCGGAGCGCGAGGCGGAGGCGGAGGCCGAGGGCUACUUCCGCAAGAUGCAGGCGCGCCGCUUCCCCGACUAGCGCGGCGGGGCCGGGGGCGGGCGGGGGGCGGGCCGAGGGCGCGGGCGGCCGCGCGGAUGCUCAAUAAAGCGGCAGAAACCGA